AGUCCUCGGAGCGCCGGGGAGGCCGCGGAGCCUCACGUGUGCCGCCCCAGCCGCUGGCGCCCGGAAGGACGCGCUGCGACCCCGUGGGAGCCGAACGCGGGAGUCGCUGCCCGAGCGGAGCUGCUCAGCCGCGGUAACGGGUCGGGGCCUCAUCGUGCAGGGGAGCGAGCGGAGGGGCGGGGCGGGGCGCGGGCGGGCUGAGGAGCCGCCGGGCUCGGGCUCCGCGCGGGGAUGUGUCUGGCCACCGCGUACUUUCGAGGGCGCCUCAACACCCGGUUUCUCUCUGCUCAAGCUGGAAGCACCUGAGGUGGGCCCCCACACGUCCCUCUGCUGUCUACACCGCCCUGUUCUCUCUUCCCUACCACCCGCCCAGGAGCUGCUGUUUUACCACUGGCCGGGAUCGAAAUUCGGGGUUCUUACUGGGACUGAUGCCCUUGGCCAGACGCACCCCCAACUGCUGUCUGCUCAGGUGUAGCCCGCGUGACUGAGUCACCGCUGCUCCAGCUGUUUCACGUCGCCGUUCCCUUUACUGAAUCCACGCAGAAGCGGGAGCUAAGAAGGGUGUGACGGGAGAGGAAAGGCGAGAAGAGCACCAAAGGGGAAAGAUCGUGAGAACUUUUUGAAACUGGGUACUCAACUUCGCCCACUUAGGCUGGCCCAGUCUGGAGCCACAGUCGUCCUCAGCCUUCAGGAAACCCCUGGGGCCUGGCCCUCCCGGCACCUGCUGCUCUCAGGCCCCCUGCCCCAGCCUCGGGGCAGUUCCAGGAAGACUCCCCCCGGCCCAGCCCAGGGCUGCAGCCACAGCUGGUCCUCAGCCCUCCGCACAUCUUUGCAGAGUUUGAUGGGGCGCCGGGCGGAUGACAGCGGGAACGGUUGUGAUCACUGGCGGAAUCCUAGCUACGGUGAUCCUCCUCUGCAUCAUUGCCGUCCUGUGCUACUGCAGGCUCCAGUAUUACUGCUGCAAGAAGAGCGGAACCGAGGUUGCAGACGAGGAGGAGGAGCGGGAGCACGACCUUCCCACGCAUCCCAGAGGCCCCACCUGCAAUGCCUGCAGCUCCCAAGCCCUGGACGGCAGAGGCAGCCUGGCGCCUCUCACCAGCGAGCCCUGCAGCCAGCCCUGUGGGGUGGCCGCGAGCCACUGCACUACCUGCUCCCCAUACAGCUCCCCCUUUUACAUACGGACGGCUGACAUGGUGCCCAAUGGGGGUGGAGGCGAGAGGCUCUCCUUUGCUCCCACAUACUACAAAGAGGGGGGACCCCCAUCCCUCAAAUUGGCAGCACCCCAGAGUUACCCGGUGACCUGGCCAGGCUCUGGGCGUGAGGCCUUCACCAAUCCAAGGGCUAUUAGUACAGACGUGUAAAUCCUUCCACCCCGACCCGCACACACACCCACACUGCUGCCCUGGCGGGGGCCAUGGGGGUGAUGAAUGACCCUCCAACAGCCCCACAUGGGUUGUUUCUGUUUCUUUGGCUUUUCUCGCUCCGCAGUGGAGGGUUUACUAGGAUUUAAGCUUUUGAGUGCAUUGAGAACCAAGACAGGGCCUGGCUCCAACUCUGUGGGCCAGAGGUGGGGGACUGCUAGGUCGAGUCUGCAGCUUCGCCAGUUUCUUGGUUGGGACACUCCUCUGGCAGCCCCAGCACCACCACAACCCCUUGCAGUGUGCCCCAGUCCCCUGGAUUCGCUGGACUGCAAAAAGGAGCACCAGGGAAAGCUCAGCAAAGGCUCAGGAGGCCUCCCGGGUCCUCGGGAGAUGAAGCAUCCGUGCCUAGGAAAAGGGGACAGAGGGCAAGGAGAGAAGUGAGAGCUACAAUUCCAGCAUUGGAGAAGCGAGGGGCGGGGCGUCAACGGCACUGCUUCAGGACGCGCUUGCUGAAACGACUCCAACAGCUAGUUCACAGCCCAGCUUUGUACGUUGGUUACCAUAGCUACUGCUGUCACUGUAGCUGCUCCCGUAGGGUCGUUGAUUCCUGAACGUAUCACAUCUCACCUGCCCCCUUCCUCGUGGGACGUGUCAAGUUGACUUUAAAGCCUAAGGUGGCUUGUGGGGACUGCACCAGAAAGUGUCUAACCUUGUGUUCCCCGAAAUCCUUUCUCUGACUUAGGAACCAGCGCCCCCUGCUGGAGAAGUUUUUUCAUUUUGUUAGCCGACUUCUGGUAGCUUAGCAAAGAGACCAGCUGACUGUCUCUCGGCCCAGCCCACCACGCCGAGUAGCUUGUGUGGAUGCAGUCCUGUGAGGGUGUGCAUAACCGUUCCCAGGUGUACGCACGCGCGCGCGCGCGCACAGACACACACACACACACACACACACACACACACACACAGUAACCACGGGUAGGCACCAGGGGCUUUGUACAUUCAGGAGCUGCAGAGAGGAAAGGUCUCCCAUGUACCAGAGAAGGAAAAGUCUGAUCCCGAAACAGCUUGAACGAAAGGUGGUUAACACGUGACCAAUCCCCAUGGCAGACAGCGGGCUGGUGAACAGGAAGAGCACAGAAUCUCUGUGGGGCGAUGCUGCAGCGGCUGAAACCACGUCAAGUCCCCCAGAGCCCGGCAUUCUAUGUAAGCAUCCACCUGUGACGCCGUGGAGCAGGAUCUUCAUUCAUCUCACCAGAGCAACAGCCCAGUCCUGAGGAUGGGAGGGACGUGACUUAGCCUUGGGAUUCCACGCUCGCCGCCCUCCCUUGGCCGCCCUACUCCCCAGUUUCCUGGCGAUGAGCCAUUUAUUGUGUCUCACACCAGCCUCAUUUCCAACUCCGACUUCCUACUUAGAAUGUGGCAGUGGCUUUGUGAGUGAGAAUCCUGAUGAGUUUUCCAGUGGCCUCUGCAGAAGCUGGCCCCCUUCUAAGGGCAUAGCUAACCCCCUUCCCACUCCUGAGUCACUGAAUUCGAGGAGGGUGGGGCAGGGAAAGGGCUGGCCCCCCUGCUGAAAUCUUGAUUCUGCAUUUGAGGAAGGUCAGGGUGCCGCUGGGGGAGCAGGGAGCGGGGAGGGAGGAAGAGGGGAAUGCACAUCUUUUGCGCCACUAUUAAGGCACCUGUCACCUUACAUCUCAAUCUGGAAUCAAAGUGCCCUGGGUUGAGAAGCAGACCUGGGCUCUGGUCACACUUUGGUCACUCAUUAGCUCUAGGACCAGUCACUAAUCUCUGAGACUCCAUUUUCUCCAGGGAAACGAGGCUUGCCCAGAUAGACUAACAACCCUUUAGUGCUCCAAGAAGUGAGAAUUUCCGAAAAAGAUCUGCCGGCCCAGAGCACUCCCUCUUGCCCUAAUCCUGGCAGGGUCUGGAUGUAUUUACCCAACUCUGAUCUUGCGUGCAGGGAUGCUUGCUGAUGGAUGAAAGACCACAAUAAAACAAGAUUAGCAGCAAAACAA